AGGCAGGGCUGCAGAUGCGAGGCCCAGCUGUACCUCGCGUGUCCCGGGUCGGGAGUCGGAGACGCAGGUGCAGGAGAGUGCGGGGCAAGUAGCGCAUUUUCUCUUUGCAUUCUCGAGAUCGCUUAGCCGCGCUUUAAAAAGGUUUGCAUCAGCUGUGAGUCCAUCUGACAAGCGAGGAAACUAAGGCUGAGAAGUGGGAGGCGUUGCCAUCUGCAGGCCCAGGCAACCUGCUACGGGAAGACCGGGGACCAAGACCUCUGGGUUGGCUUUCCUAGACCCGCUCGGGUCUUCGGGUGUCGCGAGGAAGGGCCCUGCUCCUUUCGUUCCCUGCACCCCUGGCCGCUGCAGGUGGCUCCCUGGAGGAGGAGCUCCCACGCGGAGGAGGAGCCAGGGCAGCUGGGAGCGGGGACACCAUCCUCCUGGAUAAGAGGCAGAGGCCGGGAGGAACCCCGUCAGCCGGGCGGGCAGGAAGCUCUGGGAGUAGCCUCAUGGAAGAGAAGCAGAUCCUGUGCGUGGGGCUAGUGGUGCUGGACGUCAUCAGCCUGGUGGACAAGUACCCUAAGGAGGACUCGGAGAUAAGGUGUUUGUCCCAGAGAUGGCAGCGCGGAGGCAACGCGUCCAACUCCUGCACCGUUCUCUCCCUGCUCGGAGCCCCCUGUGCCUUCAUGGGCUCAAUGGCUCCUGGCCAUGUUGCUGACAGUUUUGUCCUGGAUGACCUCCGCCGCUAUUCUGUGGACCUACGCUACACAGUCUUUCAGACCACAGGCUCCGUCCCCAUCGCCACGGUCAUCAUCAACGAGGCCAGUGGUAGCCGCACCAUCCUAUACUAUGACAGCUUCCUGGUGGCCGACUUCAGGCGGCGGGGCGUGGACGUGUCUCAGGUGGCCUGGCAGAGCAAGGGGGACACCCCCAGCUCCUGCUGCAUCAUCAACAACUCCAAUGGCAACCGUACCAUUGUGCUCCAUGACACGAGCCUGCCAGAUGUGUCUGCUACAGACUUUGAGAAGGUUGAUCUGACCCAGUUCAAGUGGAUCCACAUUGAGGGCCGGAACGCAUCGGAGCAGGUGAAGAUGCUGCAGCGGAUAGACGCACACAACACCAGGCAGCCUCCAGAGCAGAAGAUCCGGGUGUCCGUGGAGGUGGAGAAGCCACGAGAGGAGCUCUUCCAGCUGUUUGGCUACGGAGACGUGGUGUUUGUCAGCAAAGAUGUGGCCAAGCACUUGGGGUUCCAGUCAGCAGAGGAAGCCUUGAGGGGCUUGUAUGGUCGUGUGAGGAAAGGGGCUGUGCUUGUCUGUGCCUGGGCUGAGGAGGGCGCCGACGCCCUGGGCCCUGAUGGCAAAUUGCUCCACUCGGAUGCUUUCCCGCCACCCCGCGUGGUGGAUACACUGGGAGCUGGAGACACCUUCAAUGCCUCCGUCAUCUUCAGCCUCUCCCAGGGGAGGAGCGUGCAGGAAGCACUGAGAUUCGGGUGCCAGGUGGCCGGCAAGAAGUGUGGCCUGCAGGGCUUUGAUGGCAUCGUGUGAGAGCAGGUGCCGGCUCCUCACACACCAUGGAGACUACCAUUGCGGCUGCAUCGCCUUCUCCCCUCCAUCCAGCCUGGCGUCCAGGUUGCCCUGUUCAGGGGACAGAUGCAAGCUGUGGGGAGGACUCUGCCUGUGUCCUGUGUUCCCCACAGGGAGAGGCUCUGGGGGGAUGGCUGGGGGAUGCAGAGCCUCAGAGCAAAUAAAUCUUCCUCAGAGCCAGCUUCUCCUCUCAAUGUCUGAACUGCUCUGGCUGGGCAUUCCUGAGGCUCUGACUCUUCGAUCCUCCCUCUUUGUGUCCAUUCCCCAAAUUAACCUCUCCGCCCAGGCCCAGAGGAGGGGCUGCCUGGGCUAGAGCAGCGAGAAGUGCCCUGGGCUUGCCACCAGCUCUGCCCUGGCUGGGGAGGACACUCGGUGCCCCACACCCAGUGAACCUGCCAAAGAAACCGUGAGAGCUCUUCGGGGCCCUGCGUUGUGCAGACUCUAUUCCCACAGCUCAGAAGCUGGGAGUCCACACCGCUGAGCUGAACUGACAGGCCAGUGGGGGGCAGGGGUGCGCCUCCUCUGCCCUGCCCACCAGCCUGUGAUUUGAUGGGGUCUUCAUUGUCCAGAAAUACCUCCUCCCGCUGACUGCCCCAGAGCCUGAAAGUCUCACCCUUGGAGCCCACCUUGGAAUUAAGGGCGUGCCUCAGCCACAAAUGUGACCCAGGAUACAGAGUGUUGCUGUCCUCAGGGAGGUCCGAUCUGGAACACAUAUUGGAAUUGGGGCCAACUCCAAUAUAGGGUGGGUAAGGCCUUAUAAUGUAAAGAGCAUAUAAUGUAAAGGGCUUUAGAGUGAGACAGACCUGGAUUAAAAUCUGCCAUUUAAUUAGCUGCAUAUCACCUUAGGGUACAGCACUUAACGCAAUCUGCCUCAAUUUCUUCAUCUGUCAAAUGGAACCAAUUCUGCUUGGCUACAGAAUUAUUGUGAGGAUAAAAUCAUAUAUAAAAUGCCCAGCAUGAUGCCUGAUGUGUA